CUUUCCGGAGCGCGGGCGCGCGGUGGCGGGAAUUUCGCCUGUUUGCGGUUUAGACCCCAAAGAUUCCUGUUGGUGGUCUGGGUCACAGGAGGCAGGUUUCGGGAGCUGGAAAUGUGAGCGGGUACGACAGGCACCGCGGGUAACCGACGCCCCGGGUCCUUGCUGCAGCCGGGUACGCGGGAUACCGGCACCCCGCCUUCUCCGCCCGAGUGCUGCCAGGCGUGGGCCUGGAAUCUCUUCACACCUUCUCUUUGGAGCCCUUAAUGAUACGACGAACCCCAAGUGUUUCAGAACAUGAAGUAAACAAUGGAGAACUGUUCUGCUGCAUCGACGUUCCUGACUGACAGCUUAGAGCUGGAGCUGGGGACGGAAUGGUGCAAACCUCCUUACUUUUCUUGUGCUGUUGACAACAGAGGAGGAGGAAAACAUUUUUCUGGAGAAUCCUACCUCUGCAGCGGAGCCCUUAAGCGAUUGAUUUUGAAUCUUGACCCUUUACCAACUAAUUUUGAAGAAGAUACCUUGGAAAUAUUUGGCAUUCAGUGGGUUACUGAAACAGCAUUAGUGAAUUCAUCUAGAGAACUCUUUCAUUUAUUCAGGCAACAACUGUACAACUUGGAAACCUUGUUACAGUCCAGUUGUGAUUUUGGGAAGGUAUCAACUCUACACUGCAAAGCAGACAAUAUUAGGCAGCAGUGUGUACUAUUUCUCCAUUAUGUUAAAGUUUUCAUCUUCAGGUAUCUGAAAGUACAGAAUGCUGAGAGUCAUGUUCCUGUCCAUCCUUAUGAGGCUUUGGAGGCUCAGCUUCCCUCAGUGUUGAUUGAUGAGCUUCAUGGAUUACUCUUGUAUAUUGGACACCUAUCUGAACUUCCCAGUGUUAAUAUAGGAGCAUUUGUAAAUCAAAACCAGAUUAAGCUUUUUCCACCGUCAUGGCAUUUAUUACAUCUCCACUUGGAUAUACAUUGGCUGGUGCUAGAAAUUCUUUACAUGCUGGGUGAAAAAUUGAAACAAGUUGUAUAUGGUCAUCAGUUUAUGAAUCUGGCAAGUGACAAUUUAACCAACAUCAGCCUAUUUGAAGAACAUUGUGAAACUCUCCUUUGUGAUUUAAUAAGCCUGUCACUCAACAGGUACGACAAGGUUAGGUCUUCUGAAUCAUUAAUGAGUGACCAGUGUCCAUGUUUAUGCAUUAAAGAAUUAUGGGUUCUACUUAUUCAUCUUCUAGACCACAGAAGUAAAUGGUUUGUCUCGGAAUCAUUUUGGAACUGGUUGAAUAAACUACUUAAAACACUGCUUGAAAAAUCAAGUGACCGAAGAAGAUCCUCUAUGCCUGUAAUCCAGUCCAGGGAUCCAUUAGGUUUUAGUUGGUGGAUUAUUACUCAUGUAGCAUCAUUUUACAAGUUUGAUCGCCAUGGAGUACCAGAUGAAAUGAGAAAAGUGGAAUCAAAUUGGAACUUUGUAGAAGAACUGCUGAAAAAGUCCAUCAGUGUUCAGGGUGUCAUUCUAGAAGAACAAUUACGAAUGUAUCUUCACUGUUGUUUGACACUUUGUGAUUUCUGGGAGCCAAACAUUGCAAUUGUUACCAUUUUAUGGGAAUAUUAUAGUAAGAACCUGAAUAGUUCCUUCAGUAUUUCUUGGCUUCCUUUUAAAGGCCUUGCUAAUACCAUGAAGUCACCCUUGUCUAUGCUUGAAAUGGUGAAGACUUGCUGUUGCGAUAAACAAGAUCAGGAACUAUAUAAAUCCAGCAGUAGUUAUACUAUUUUUCUUUGUAUUCUGGCAAAAGUUGUUAAAAAAGCAAUGAAGAGCAAUGGCCCUCAUCCUUGGAAACAAGUCAAAGGAAGAAUAUAUUCAAAAUUCCAUCAAAAAAGAAUGGAAGAACUAACUGAAGUUGGUCUACAGAACUUUUUUAGCCUUUUUCUACUGUUAGCAGCUGUUGCAGAGGUAGAAGAUGUUGCAAGUCAUGUUUUAGACCUCCUGAAUUUCCUCAAGCCUGCUUUUGUAACGUCUCAGAGAGCCCUCAUUUGGAAGGGUCACAUGGCCUUCCUCUUGAUGUAUGCCCAGAAAAAUCUGGACAUUGGUGUUUUGGCUGAGAAAUUUUCAUGUGCUUUCCGGGAGAAAGCAAAGGAAUUCUUGGUGUCUAAGAAUGAGGAAAUGGUACAGAGACAGACUAUCUGGACCCUUCUUUCCAUAUACAUUGAUGGUGUUCAAGAAGUGUUUGAGACCAGCUAUUGCUUGUAUCCUUCCCAUGAAAAACUGCUUAAUGAUGGAUUUAGUAUGCUUCUGCGAGCAUGUCGAGAAUCUGAACUUAGGACAGUAUUGAGCUUCCUACAAGCUGUUCUGGCCAGAAUCAGGAGUAUGCAUCAACAAUUGUGUCAGGAACUUCAAAGGGACAAUGUGGACCUAUUUGUACAGUCUUCAUUAUCGGCUAAAGAGCGCCACCUUGCUGCAGUUGCCAGUGCACUGUGGAGACAUUUCUUUUCAUUUUUGAAGAGUCAGAGAAUGUCACAGGUAGUGCCUUUCUCACAACUUGCGGAUGCAGCUGCAGACUUUACUUUGCUAGCAAUGGACAUGCCAAGCACAGCUCCAUCAGAUUUUCAGCCUCAGCCAGUUAUAUCAAUUAUUCAACUUUUUGGUUGGGAUGAUAUCAUCUGCCCUCAAGUUGUAGCAAGAUAUUUAAGUCAUGUCCUACAAAAUAGCACAUUAUGUGAAGCACUUUCUCAUUCAGGCUAUGUAUCUUUUCAAGCCUUAACCGUAAGAUCAUGGAUUCGUUGUGUUUUGCAAAUGUAUAUUAAAAACCUCUCUGGGCCUGAUGAUUUGCUCAUAGAUAAAAAUCUGGAAGAGGCAGUUGAAAAAGAGUACAUGAAACAGUUGGUCAAACUGACAAGAUUACUAUUUAAUCUCUCAGAAGUAAAGAGUAUUUUCUCAAAGGCCCAAGUUGAAUAUUUAUCCAUCUCAGAAGACCCUAAAAAAGCACUUGUUCGAUUCUUUGAGGCUGUUGGUGUAACUUACGGGAACGUCCAGACACUUUCUGAUAAAUCUGCCAUGGUCACAAAGUCCUUGGAAUACCUUGGUGAAGUAUUAAAAUAUAUUAAGCCUUAUUUGGGAAAAAAAGUUUUCAGUGCAGGGCUGCAGCUGACUUAUGGAAUGAUGGGAAUUCUUGUGAAAUCAUGGGCACAAAUCUUUGCCACUUCUAAAGCCCAAAAAUUACUAUUCCGGAUCAUAGAUUGUUUACUGCUGCCACAUGCAGUAUUACAGCAAGAGAAGGAACUGCCUGCACCUAUGUUGUCAGCAAUUCAGAAAAGUCUUCCUUUGUAUCUCCAGGGCAUGUGUAUCGUGUGUUGUCAAUCUCAAAAUCCGAAUGCCUAUUUGAAUCAAUUGCUAGGGAAUGUUAUUGAGCAGUAUAUUGGGCGAUUUCUUCCAGCUUCACCAUAUGUUUCAGAUCUUGGACAACAUCCUGUUUUGCUGGCAUUGAGAAACACAGCCACUAUUCCACCAAUAUCAUCUCUAAAGAAAUGCAUUGUGCAAGUCAUAAGGAAAUCCUACCUUGAGUAUAAGGGGUCCUCACCUCCUCCUCGCUUAGCAUCCAUUCUGGCCUUCAUCCUCCAACUCUUCAAGGAAACUAACACAGACAUUUAUGAAGUUGAACUACUCCUCCCUGGCAUUUUAAAAUGCUUGGUGUUAGUCAGUGAACCACAAGUUAAAAGGCUGGCCACAGAGAACCUGCAAUACAUGGUAAAAGCCUGCCAAGUGGGGUCAGAAGAAGAACCUUCCUCCCAGCUGACUUCUGUGUUUAGGCAGUUUAUCCAGGAUUAUGGUAUGAGGUACUAUUACCAGGUUUACAGCAUUUUAGAAACAGUAGCAACAUUGGACCAGCAGGUUGUCAUCCACUUGAUUUCUACCCUUACUCAGUCUCUGAAGGAUUCAGAGCAGAAAUGGGGCCUUGGCAGGAAUAUAGCACAAAGGGAAGCCUAUAGCAAACUUUUGUCUCACCUUGGACAGAUGGGACAAGAUGAGAUGCAGAGACUGGAAAAUGAUAAUACUUAAUAUAUUUUGUGAUUCAUCCUGUCUAUUAAUUAUCAGUAUCUAAAGCCACAUUGUUCCACUCUAAUUCCUACUUUUAAUUAAUUGUAUAAUGUUCUGUUUAAAAUAAUUUCUAGGAUUUUUUUUCCUUUUAUAUCUGUAAGUAAAAAAUGUAUAAAUAAGGAACUGAAGGUUAAUUAGCAACUGUGUAAUAGGAUCCUUGGAACUUUUUACAAAACUGCAUUCUACCUUGAUGAAAUUUUAGUUAAACUAAAUUAAAGAAACAUUUUCUGAGAGUGUUUUCUGUGUGUGAGUAUUAAGCAGAUACUUCAUCCAUAGACUUUUUGUUGUAGUAUGACUUCCUGCCUCCCUGCCUUGUGACUGAUUUGUCAUGUUUAUUUUUUAUUUUUACAAUAAUAGUUAUGUUUUAAAAUGAUACUUUUUCAAAGUACCUGGCUACCCUAUACUGUGUUUUUGGUGGGGGAAAGGUGUUGGGAAAUGUGACUGUGUAUUUGUUUUUCUUUUUUAUAUGUGUGAGGCAAGUUAACAAAGAAAACCCUUACAAAGCACACUUAACUGUGUUAGGAAUGAGACUGAAUCUGGCUAAAGGAUUAUACAGCUGAUAUCCAAAAAGAAGUGUAAACAUGCCAACAGGGUUUAUAUUUAGGUUCCAAGAGUUGCCAAAUUUUUUUUUUAUUCAUCCUUUCUUUUGGAGUUGUCAUUAAAAAAAAAAUCAUAUCAGGAGGAGGAAAUAAAGGAGACUUUAAGAGGAGAGUAAAUAAAAAUAUUCUAGAAAAGUAACAAUAGUAGUGGUCUGAGAAGUCAGCUGAUCCAUCUUCUUGCUCUUUAGCCAGAGCUUCUUAUAACUUAGCAUUUUAUCCAAGAAACCUGUUUAGUUUCCUUUAACAACAUUGUUUCUCAACUUUUGAACUCUUAACUCAUCCAGAUUGUUUUACCAGUUGGAGCUUGUCCUUGACUCCUUUUCCUAUUGAGCAUUAUUUGGUUGAAAGAGCUCCAGUCCUAGUUUUGGGAACCCACCUGGGUCUCAAACUCAGCUUUGCUUUAUGAUCUUGAGCUAGUUACGUAACCUUUCUCAGUCUAGUUUCUUCAUGGAGAAGAAAAGAAGAAUCCCUUUACUAUUUGACAGUGUUGUUGUGAGAAUCAAUGGGAUAAUGUACGUGAAAAUAUUUGGUGGCCCAAAUUCUGUUGGGAAAUGUACAGACACGAUUAGUUUAUUACUCGUGCACAAUUAAGGCAAAGAACACCUCUCAAUUUUAUCUUUCUCUAAUGAUAUGUCCCAGAUGAAUGAUCCCACUUUCCAAUGUUUUCUUACAUCAUGUUUUCUAACUUUGAAGUACUUUGUUUCCUUCUUGGGAUUAUAGUCUUUAUCAUGGUUCUACUCUUCCUUCAAGAAAACAUUUCAACCCUUCUCUGGCUCAAGGAGUAUCUUUAAAAAUGAAAUACUUUGCAAUCAGUAUUCUGUAGUUAAUAGCGUUCUCUUAAUUAUAAUCUGUGAAAUCCAAAGGAGUGUCUGUUAUUUUCAUAACAUAUAAAUGGUCCUUCUCUCAAAUCAGCUUCAUCAAAGGGAAUAAAUGAAAGCUUAAGGCUGUUUAAUAGACUUCAUAACACUGAAUUUCUUUUCAUCAUGAUAGUGACUUACUAAACAAAUAAUGUAUGGCUUGGAAAGUUCCAGCAGUCACUAAGGAGUUUUAUCUAUUUAAGGUGAUGCCUUUAAAGAGGUUAUUUAUGUGUAUAUGUGUUUUUGUGUGUGUGUGUGUGUGUGUGUGUGUGUGUGUGUGUGUGUGGGUUUUUUUUUUCCAAAGGAGAUUGAUAAAGAUACCUUUGAGAAUCUUGCUCCUUAGAGUAUGAAAACGUUUAAAGGAUAGGAAAAGCUGCUACUGAAUCAUGCUUUAGGACAUAUAUCUAUAGAUACUAAGAAUAACUAAAAUUUGUACUUAAGAAUGGUAACAACAAAGUGUGUAACAAUAUGUGUGUGUAUUAUAUGUUUUGUAUUUAUGUAUAAGUAACUUUUUUUAAAGCUUUUUUUUAAAUUGAAAAAAGAAGAAAAUUUAUGGCUCAGUUCCUUUUUUUUAAAAUCUUCACUGAUCCUUCACUUAUUACUACAAUCUUGCCCUCUUUCAUUCCCAGACUUGGAGUCCCUUAUACCUGCUUCUUUAAUAGCCACUUUCCCUAAAUACCCUGUAAUUUCUGAGGCUGCUGCUUCUACCAGUGUAAUACAAGCCAUUGUCUUUUGGUCAAAUCUGAGUUUGUUCUCCUUUCUCAUGUUCUUUGUCCUCUCUGUGACAAUUGUAUUUUCUUUUAUCUUCCCAUCAUUUCCACAAUGGUACUGCUCCUUCCUACAUAUACAGUUGACCCUUGAGCAACACAAGUUUGAACUGUGCAGGUCCACUUAUAUGUGGAUCUAAAAUACAGUAUUUGUGGGAUGCAAAAUCUGAGUAUAUGGAGGACCAACUUUUUGUAGAGGCAGGUUCCUCAGGGUUAACUGCAGGACUUGAGUAAGUGCAGAUUAUGGUAUGCACAGGGGAUCCUGGAACCAGUCCCCAGACCAAAAAUGACCACUGUAUCUUGAGAGCACCUUCAUGGUCUUCUUUCCUGUCCCCAGUCGUAAGAUACGACCCUUCAUCUGCUUUGUCUCAACAUUCUGUUAGUGGUGAACUGAUAACUCCAGCUUUUCUCUCUCUUUUUUUUUUUUUUUUUUUUUUUGUUGUUGUUGUUGUUGUUGUUUUGAGGCAGAGUCUUGCUCUGUCGCCCAGGCUGGAGUGCAGUGGCACGAUCUCGGCUCACUGCAAGCUCUGCCUCCCGGGUUCACGCCAUUCUCCUGCCUCAGCCUCCCAAGUAGCUGGGACUACAGGUGCCCGCCACCACGCCCGGCUAAUUUUUUUUGUAUUUUUAGUAGAGACGGGGUUUCACCAUGUUGGGCUCGAUCUCCUGACCUCAUGAUCCGCCCGCCUCGGCCUCCCAAAGUGCUGGGAUUACAGGCGUGAUGAGCCACCUAGUGCUAAUUCAUCUCUAAACCUCUGUAGUUGGAGUCUCCUGAAAUCUCAGACUACCUCCUGCUUUCAUUUUCUACCCAGGGAAUACACUAUUGUCCUAAGUUAUUUAGCCUUGAAAUGUCAGAGGCAUUUUAGGUUCUUCAUGUUUCUCCCACUUUCAGUUGAUUACCAUUACAGGAUCUUAGGCUUCUUUUUAUCUUUUUGCAGUGCCUUGCAUCCACUGGUUGUUUGUUUUUUCUGUUGGGCACUACUUAUUUCCUUACCUCUGGUUUCUUCUCCUACAGCUUAUGUUCUGAAAUGUGUAUUCCUAAAAUACUGUUUUCCUCUUGUUACUUUUCUGCUCGAGGACUUCCAGUAACUUACCAUUGUUUAUAAGGUGAUGUUCAAACCCUUCAGUCUGGAGACUUUCUGCCACCUAUCUGACUGUACCUUUAUCUUCAAGCUUAUCUCUUUCCAAACAAGAGGCUCAUUUAGCAGCUUUCUCUGAUUGCCAUGUUCAUCCUACACUCAGCCUCAUUCAGUUUACAGCAUGGAAACUGUAUAGGACCUCUUUCCUAUAGAAAUUGAAGACACUUAAAUAGGAAGAAAAUUAAAAUAUACAUUUGGAUACAUGAGUAUUCCAGUCAAAUAAUAUCUAUAAAAUACCAGAUAGAGUAUAAAAGACAACUGAAGGACAACAGAGUGAUGAAAGGACUUUAUUAGGCAUUUGGAUUUGGUUAUGAUUUAAAUUUCAAUUUAAUUAGAACGUUUCCAUGGCAAGGAAGGAAGCAUGGAGGACUGUGGAAAAGUCAUUCAGUAUUGAGUUCAUUUGCAUUAGAGGAAUUUCAUAGUUUAAAACUUGUAUAUCUUUACCUAUCCUUCGUAUGUUUUCUUCUUAAGCAUAUUUGACUUUUUCUACCUCAGCAUCUGUAUAAGAAAAUAUUUGUGAGUCAGAUGUUUGUGGGUUUUCCUUACCUAUUAUUAUUUUCUUCCAUGCUUUACAACACAUUUUUUAAACUACCUUGUUCUUAAAUAAUUACACGGACCUGCUUCUGUGUACUUUCACAGAAUCUUUGACAGUUAAAAAUUGUAUGUUAUAUAAAAAUUUGACAAGCUUCUACAGUUAGGAAAAGCCUUUAGAAAUCUGCCUUCCCCAAACCGUAUGUUAUCAUAGCACUCAUGUCUCCCCAUGUCUAAAAGGUAAAUAGAUACAGAAACCUCACCAAAAGUUGAAUCAUCUGUACUAAACCACUGCUUUUUUAUCCAGACUUUUUAUAUAAAUCUUUUAUUUUCCAAAAAACUGAUCUUUUACCUACCCCUCUUAGAGUUAAAAAUAUUGCCUGUCAGGCAAGAGUAUAGUAUGCCAAUAUAAAUAAUAUGCUUUAUUUGGUUAGAAACAGUUGGUUUGGGAAGCUAGCAACAUAGCAUAUUCUUUACAAAUUUAAUAAGGUGUAUUUUGAUACUGUGAUAACCUGCAUUGUAAAUUACCAAAUGGUUGGAAUUGACCAGUUUAUACUUAUUAAAAUUUUUGAUGUGCCAAUGGCUAUCCAAUUCAUUGCAUUUGUGAAUUGUGCUUUUAGAAAAAUUGUGGACAUUUUAGUUUUAUAUACAUAUUUAUGAGUUAUUUGUGCAUAUGAUAAAAUUAUAUAUAAUAAUAAAAGUAUAUAUGUAACUUA